AAGACCCAGACUCUUCCCUAGGCUGGGAGAGACUCGGCGGUUGAAAGCAGGGAGGCGCUACAGGAGAGAAAGGGCUGAACCCCCGCUUCCGCAGAUUUCACCUAUUUUUCAGUUUGCCUGGAGCAGGCCACGCAAAUUCCCUUCCCUUGAAGGCCCAAGGAGCGUCUGGUAGAUUGCUGAUUCUCUGCCCAUCACCGCUUCUGGAAGUGGAGCCGCCACCAAAAUGCAGAUUUUCGUGAAAACCCUUACGGGGAAGACCAUCACCCUCGAGGUUGAACCCUCGGAUACGAUAGAAAAUGUAAAGGCCAAGAUCCAGGAUAAGGAAGGAAUUCCUCCUGAUCAGCAGAGACUGAUCUUUGCUGGCAAGCAGCUGGAAGAUGGACGUACUUUGUCUGACUACAAUAUUCAAAAGGAGUCUACUCUUCAUCUUGUGUUGAGACUUCGUGGUGGUGCUAAGAAAAGGAAGAAGAAGUCUUACACCACUCCCAAGAAGAAUAAGCACAAGAGAAAGAAGGUUAAGCUGGCUGUCCUGAAAUAUUAUAAGGUGGAUGAGAAUGGCAAAAUUAGUCGCCUUCGUCGAGAGUGCCCUUCUGAUGAAUGUGGUGCUGGGGUGUUUAUGGCAAGUCACUUUGACAGACAUUAUUGUGGCAAAUGUUGUCUGACUUACUGUUUCAACAAACCAGAAGACAAGUAACUGUAUGAGUUAAUAAAAGACAUGAACUAACAUUUAUUGUUGGGUUUUAUUGCAGUAAAAAGAAUGGUUUUUAAGCACCAAAUUGAUGGUCACACCAUUUCCUUUUAGUAGUGCUACUGCUAUCGCUGUGUGAAUGUUGCCUCUGGGGAUUAUGUGACCCAGUGGUUCUGUAUACCUGCCAGGUGCCAACCACUUGUAAAGGUCUUGAUAUUUUCAAUUCUUAGACUACCUAUACUUUGGCAGAAGUUAUAUUUAAUGUAAGUUGUCUAAAUAUAA